AAGCAAGCCUGGGCAAUGGCGGGCGCCCCUCCCCCAGCCUCGCUGCCGCCUUGCAGUUUGAUCUCAGACUGCUGUGCUAGCAGUCAGCGAGACUCCGUGGGCGUAGGACCCUCUGAGCCAGGUGCGAGAUAUAAUCUCGUGGUGCGCCGUUUUUUAAGCCGGUUGGAAAAGUGCGGUAUUCGGGUGGGAGUGACCCGAUUUUCCAGGUGCCGUUCGUCACCCCUUUCUUUGACUAGGAAAGGGAACUCCCUGACCCCUUGCGCUUCCCAAGUGAGGCAAUGCCUCGCCCUGCUUUGGGUCGCGUCGGUGUGCGCACCCACUGACCUGCGCCCACUGUCUGGCACUCCCUAGUGAGAUGAACCCGGUACCUCAGAUGGAAAUGCAGAAAUCACCCGUCUUCUGCGUCGCUCAGGCUGGGAGCUGUGGACCGGAGCUGUUCCUAUUCGGCCAUCUUGGCUCCUCGCAGUUCAUUGUUUGUGGGGUUAAUUGGAAGCAGCUGCAGCAGGAGUAUUCACAAGAAAACAGGACACACCCACAGCCAAGCUAUAGGAAGGUCAUCAUCCUAGCAUGUACAAGAAAGCGUCCCUGGAUACUGGACAGAUGGCGUUUACCUUGGCCCAACUUGAGUCCUUGGAGAUUUGCCUGAAAGAAGCAGAAGAAAAGGCUAAAGCUUUAUCUGAACAGCUUUCAGUCUCUGAAGGAACAAAAUCAAAACUGCUUGAACAAGUAUCCCGGCUGGAGGAAAAACUGGAGGCUGUGGACCACAAGGAAGCCAGUGGGGGACCAUAUGAAAAAAUGGUUCUUGUGAAAGACCAGUGCAUCCAGAAAUUGCAAGCUGAAGUAAAAGCUUCCCAGGAGCAACUUAUAGCCCAGAAACUAAAGCAUGAAAAGAAAGUGAAAAAACUACAGACUGAUUUGGCAACAGCUAAUGCCAUCACAGUUCUGGAACUCAAUGAGAAGAUAAAGACUCUAUAUGAAGGAAAGCCAGCCCCUAGAGACCUCUGUUUGCAAAUGAAAGAUGCUCCAGUCAUAACAGCUUAAGGAGAAAGGGUGAUUUACCGGCACAUGUAAACAAACCAAGAGAGAGCAUUGCACUAGCCUUGGAGUAAGAUGGAUUCCAGUCUAAAGUACCAUCAGGAAACACUGUGUCACUCAUCUCUGCUUCUCUCUAAAGAUGGAUUCCAGUCUAAAGUACCAUCAGGAAACGGUGUCACUCACCUCUGCUUCUCUCUGCAUUGAGACUUGAUUCUCUCAGGCUAGACUUCAGAAGAGAAUGGAAAUAUGGCCACAAGCAGCUAUGGGCUGCCCUCCUUAUCAUAUAAUCUCCAGGGAAGAAAGAAAGCAUUUUUCCACUAACUCUAGUUGGAAAGUGCAAGAAAGAACUCAGUCCUAGCUUAGGUUGGGUACCCAUCUGUGGAUAUGAACCAAUCUUUGUGGCCAGGGCUGAGGAAAUAAGGUUGAACAAACUGUGGUCAUGUCCCCACCACUGGGUGGCAGGGUAGAGGGAGUAAAUGUGGGGAAGGAGAAUGCUCCAGCUGGCAGCUCCUACGAAAAGCACAGAGCUGGAUUAGGAGAAAUCCACUUUCUUAAAGGAAUAUCUCAUUACUGGAAAGGAGUGAUAGGCAAAACCAAUAUCUCCUAGCCAGGCAUGGUGAUGCAUCCCUGUAAUCCCAGCUACUUGGGAGGCUGAGGCAUGAGAAUUGCUUGAACCUGGGAGGCAGAGGUUGCAGUGAGCUGAGAUCGUGCCACUGCACUCCAGUCUUGGUGAAAGAGCAAGACUCUGUCUCAAAAAAUAAAAUGAAAUUGCCUUGGCGAUGCGGGCUCUUUUUUGGUUCCAUAUGAACUUUAAAGUAGUUUUUUCCAAUUCUGUGAAGAAAGUCAUUGGUAGCUUGAUGGGGAUGGCAUUGAAUCUGUAAAUUACCUUGGGCAGUAUGGCCAUUUUCAUGAUAUUGAUUCUUCCUACCCAUGAGCAUGGAAUGUUCUUCCAUUUGUUUGUAUCCUCUUUUAUUUCCUUGAGCAGUGGUUUGUAGUUCUCCUUGAAGAGGUCCUUCACAUCCCUUGUAAGUAGGAUUCCUAGGUAUUUUAUUCUCUUUGAAGCAAUUGUGAAUGGGAGUUCACUCAUGAUUUGGCUCUCUGUUUGUCUGUUGUUGGUGUAUAAGAAUGCUUGUGAUUUUUGUACAUUGAUUUUGUAUCCUGAGACUUUGCUGAAGUUGCUUAUCAGCUUAAGGAGAUUUUGGGCUGAGACAAUGGGGUUUUCUAGAGCAAUCCUAAGCCAAAAGAACAAAGCUGGAGGCAUCACACUACCUGACUUCAAACUAUACUACAAGGCUACAGUAACCAAAACAGCAUGGUACUGGUACCAAAACAGAGAUAUAGAUCAAUGGAACAGAACAGAGCCCUCAGAAGUAACACCGCAUAUCUACAACUAUCUGAUCUUUGACAAACCUGAGAAAAACAAGCAAUGGGGAAAGGAUUCCCUAUUUAAUAAAUGGUGCUGGGAAAACUGGCUAGCCAUAUGUAGAAAGCUGAAACUGGAUCCCUUCCUUACACCUUAUACAAAAAUCAAUUCAAGAUGGAUUAAAGACUUAAACAUUAGACCUAAAACCAUAAAAACCCUAGAAGAAAACCUAGGCAUUACCAUUCAGGACAUAGGCACGGGCAAGGACUUCAUGUCUAAAACACCAAAAGCAAUGGCAACAAAAGACAAAAUUGACAAAUGGGAUCUAAUUAAACUAAAGAGCUUCUGCACAGCAAAAGAAACUACCAUCAGAGUGAACAGGCAACCUACAAAAUGGGAGAAAAUUUUCGCAACCUACUCAUCUGACAAAGGGCUAAUAUCCAGAAUCUACAAUGAACUCAAACAAAUUUACAAGAAAAAAACAAACAACCCCAUCAAAAAGUGGGCGAAGGACAUGAACAGACACUUCUCAAAAGAAGACAUUUAUGCAGCCAAAAAACACAUGAAAAAAUGCUCAUCAUCACUGGCCAUCAGAGAAAUGCAAAUCAAAACCACAAUGAGAUACCAUCUCACACCAGUUAGAAUGGCUAUCAUUAAAAAGUCAGGAAACAACAGGUGCUGGAGAGGAUGUGGAGAAAUAGGAACACAUUUACACUGUUGGUGGGACUGUAAACUAGUUCAACCAUUGUGGAAGUCAGUGUGGCGAUUCCUCAGGGAUCUAGAACUGGAAAUACCAUCCCAUUACUGGGUAUAUACCCAGCCAUCCCAUUACUGGGUAUAUACCCAAAGGACUAUAAAUCAUGCUGCUAUAAAGACACAUGCACACGUAUGUUUAUUGCGGCAUUAUUCACAAUAGCAAAGACUUGGAACCAACCCAAAUGUUCAACAAUGAUAGACUGGAUUAAGAAAAUGUGGCACAUAUACACCAUGGAAUACUAUGCAGCCAUAAAAAGUGAUGAGUUCAUGUCCUUUGUAGGGACAUGGAUGAAAUUGGAAACCAUCAUUCUCAGUAAACUAUCCCAAGAACAAAAAACCAAACACUGCAUAUUCUCACUCAUAGGUGGGAAUUGAACAAUGAGAUCACAUGGACACAGGAAGGGGAAUAUCACACUCUGGGGACUGUGGUGGGGUGGGGGGAGGGGGGAGGGAUAGCACUGGGAGAUAUACCUAAUGCUAGAUGACGAGUUAGUGGGUGCAGCGCACCAGCAUGGCACAUGUAUACAUAUGUAACUAACCUGCACAAUGUGCACAUGUACCCUAAAACUUAAAGUAUAAUAAAAUAAAUAAAUAAAUAAAAUGAAAAUAAA